CCCCGCAGCGCCGGAGUCAAAGCCGGUUCCCGGCCCAGUCCCGUCCUGCAGCAGUCUGCCUCCUCUUUCAACAUGACAGAUGCCGCUGUGUCCUUCGCCAAGGACUUCCUGGCAGGUGGAGUGGCCGCAGCCAUCUCCAAGACGGCGGUAGCGCCCAUCGAGCGGGUCAAGCUGCUGCUGCAGGUGCAGCAUGCCAGCAAGCAGAUCACUGCAGAUAAGCAAUACAAAGGCAUUAUAGACUGCGUGGUCCGUAUUCCCAAGGAGCAGGGAGUUCUGUCCUUCUGGCGCGGUAACCUGGCCAAUGUCAUCAGAUACUUCCCCACCCAGGCUCUUAACUUCGCCUUCAAAGAUAAAUACAAGCAGAUCUUCCUGGGUGGUGUGGACAAGAGAACCCAGUUUUGGCUCUACUUUGCAGGGAAUCUGGCAUCGGGUGGUGCCGCAGGGGCCACAUCCCUGUGUUUUGUGUACCCUCUUGAUUUUGCCCGUACCCGUCUAGCAGCUGAUGUGGGUAAAGCUGGAGCUGAAAGGGAAUUCCGAGGCCUCGGUGACUGCCUGGUUAAGAUCUACAAAUCUGAUGGGAUUAAGGGCCUGUACCAAGGCUUUAACGUGUCUGUGCAGGGUAUUAUCAUCUACCGAGCCGCCUACUUCGGUAUCUAUGACACUGCAAAGGGAAUGCUUCCGGAUCCCAAGAACACUCACAUCGUCAUCAGCUGGAUGAUCGCACAGACUGUCACUGCUGUUGCCGGGUUGACUUCCUAUCCAUUUGACACUGUUCGCCGCCGCAUGAUGAUGCAGUCAGGGCGCAAAGGAACUGACAUCAUGUACACAGGCACGCUUGACUGCUGGCGGAAGAUUGCUCGUGAUGAAGGAGGCAAAGCUUUUUUCAAGGGUGCAUGGUCCAAUGUUCUCAGAGGCAUGGGUGGUGCUUUUGUGCUUGUCUUGUAUGAUGAAAUCAAGAAGUACACAUAAGUUAUUUCCUAGGAUUUUUCCCCCUGUGAACAGGCAUGUUGUAUUAUAUAACAUAUCUUGAGCAUUCUUGACAGACUCCUGGCUGUCAGUUUCUCAGUGGCAACUAUUUACUGGUUGAAAAUGGGAAGCAAUAAUAUUCAUCUGACCAGUUUUCUCUUAAAGCCAUUUCCAUGAUGAUGAUGAUGGGACUCAAUUGUAUUUUUUAUUUCAGUCACUCCUGAUAAAUAACAAAUUUGGAGAAAUAAAAAUAUCUAAAAUAAAUUUUGUCUGCAGUAUAUUUUCAUAUAAAAAUGCAUAUUUGAGUGCUACAUUCGAAUAAAUACUACCUUUUUAGUGAA